ACACAGAGCCUGUAGACCUGAGUGGAUGGACACUGCCUCUUAGAACUAGAACUUAGAACUUUAUCUUGAAAAUGUACCACUGUUGCAGAAGCUCCUCACAGAGUAUGUGUCAGGCAUUUUUAACCUGCUAAAGGCAAGAAGAAGUGUUCACCACAUAGUUGCAAAGGUCUUCAACUUGCCACAGCCAACAGAAAAAUCAAAAUGAUUGAACCCUUUGGGAAUCAGUAUAUUGUGGCCAGGCCAGUGUAUUCUACAAAUGCUUUUGAGGAAAAUCAUAAAAAGACAGGAAGACAUCAUAAGACAUUUCUGGAUCAUCUCAAAGUGUGUUGUAGCUGUUCCCCACAAAAGGCCAAGAGAAUUGUCCUCUCUUUGUUCCCCAUAGCAUCUUGGUUGCCAGCAUACCGGCUUAAAGAAUGGUUGCUCAGUGAUAUUGUUUCUGGUAUCAGCACAGGGAUUGUGGCCGUACUACAAGGUUUAGCAUUUGCUCUGCUGGUCGACAUUCCCCCAGUCUAUGGGUUGUAUGCAUCCUUUUUCCCAGCCAUAAUCUACCUUUUCUUCGGCACUUCCAGACACAUAUCCGUGGGUCCGUUUCCGAUUCUGAGUAUGAUGGUGGGACUAGCAGUUUCAGGAGCAGUUUCAAAAGCAGUCCCAGAUCGCAAUGCAACUACUUUGGGAUUGCCUAACAACUCGAAUAAUUCUUCACUACUGGAUGACGAGAGGGUGAGGGUGGCGGCGGCGGCAUCAGUCACAGUGCUUUCUGGAAUCAUCCAGUUGGCUUUUGGGAUUCUGCGGAUUGGAUUUGUAGUGAUAUACCUGUCUGAGUCCCUCAUCAGUGGCUUCACUACUGCUGCUGCUGUUCAUGUUUUGGUUUCCCAACUCAAAUUCAUUUUUCAGUUGACAGUCCCGUCACACACUGAUCCAGUUUCAAUUUUCAAAGUACUAUACUCUGUAUUCUCACAAAUAGAGAAGACUAAUAUUGCAGACCUGGUGACAGCUCUGAUUGUCCUUUUGGUUGUAUCCAUUGUUAAAGAAAUAAAUCAGCGCUUCAAAGACAAACUUCCAGUGCCCAUUCCAAUCGAAUUCAUUAUGACCGUGAUUGCAGCAGGUGUAUCCUACGGCUGUGACUUUAAAAACAGGUUUAAAGUGGCUGUGGUUGGGGACAUGAAUCCUGGAUUUCAGCCCCCUAUUACACCUGACGUGGAGACUUUCCAAAACACCGUAGGAGAUUGCUUCGGCAUCGCAAUGGUUGCAUUUGCAGUGGCCUUUUCAGUUGCCAGCGUCUAUUCCCUCAAAUACGAUUAUCCACUUGAUGGCAAUCAGGAGUUAAUAGCCUUGGGACUGGGUAACAUAGUCUGUGGAGUAUUCAGAGGAUUUGCUGGGAGUACUGCCCUCUCCAGAUCAGCAGUUCAGGAGAGCACAGGAGGCAAAACACAGAUUGCUGGGCUUAUUGGUGCCAUCAUCGUGCUGAUUGUCGUUCUAGCCAUUGGAUUUCUCCUGGCGCCUCUACAAAAGUCCGUCCUGGCAGCUUUAGCAUUGGGAAACUUAAAGGGAAUGCUGAUGCAGUUUGCUGAAAUAGGCAGAUUGUGGCGAAAGGACAAAUAUGAUUGUUUAAUUUGGAUCAUGACCUUCAUCUUCACCAUUGUCCUGGGACUCGGGUUAGGCCUGGCAGCUAGUGUGGCAUUUCAACUGCUAACCAUCGUGUUCAGGACCCAAUUUCCAAAAUGCAGCACGCUGGCUAAUAUUGGAAGAACCAACAUCUAUAAGAAUAAAAAAGAUUAUUAUGAUAUGUAUGAGCCAGAAGGAGUGAAAAUUUUCAGAUGUCCAUCUCCUAUCUACUUUGCAAACAUUGGUUUCUUUAGGCGGAAACUUAUCGAUGCUGUUGGCUUUAGUCCACUUCGAAUUCUACGCAAGCGCAACAAAGCUUUGAGGAAAAUCCGAAAACUGCAGAAGCAAGGCUUGCUACAAGUGACACCAAAAGGAUUUAUAUGUACUGUUGACACCAUAAAAGAUUCUGACGAAGAGCUGGACAACAAUCAGAUAGAAGUACUGGACCAGCCAAUCAAUACCACAGACCUGCCUUUCCACAUUGACUGGAAUGAUGAUCUUCCUCUCAACAUUGAGGUCCCCAAAAUCAGCCUCCACAGCCUCAUUCUUGACUUUUCAGCAGUGUCCUUUCUUGAUGUUUCUUCAGUGAGGGGCCUUAAAUCGAUUUUGCAAGAAUUUAUCAGGAUCAAGGUAGAUGUGUAUAUCGUUGGAACUGAUGAUGACUUCAUUGAGAAGCUUAACCGGUAUGAAUUUUUUGAUGGUGAAGUGAAAAGCUCAAUAUUUUUCUUAACAAUCCAUGAUGCUGUUUUGCAUAUUUUGAUGAAGAAAGAUUACAGUACUUCAAAGUUUAAUCCCAGUCAGGAAAAAGAUGGAAAAAUUGAUUUUACCAUAAAUACAAAUGGAGGAUUACGUAAUCGGGUAUAUGAGGUGCCAGUUGAAACAAAAUUCUAAUCAACAUAUAAUUCAGAAGGAUCUUCAUCUGACUAUGACAUAAAAACAACUUUAUACCCAGAAAGUUAUUGAUAAGUUCAUACAUUGUACGAAGAGUAUUUUUGACAGAAUAUGUUUCAAACUUUGGAACAAGAUGGUUCUAGCAUGGCAUAUUUUUCACAUAUCUAGUAUGAAAUUAUAUAAGUAUUCUAAAUUUUAUAUCUUGUAGCUUUAUCAAAGGGUGAAAAUUAUUUUGUUCAUACAUAUUUUUGUAGCACUGACAGAUUUCCAUCCUAGUCACUACCUUCAUGCAUAGGUUUAGCAGUAUAGUGGCGCCACUGUUUUGAAUCUCAUAAUUUAUACAGGUCAUAUUAAUAUAUUUCCAUUAAAAAAUCAGUUGUACAGUG